UUAUCCUGACACGCCCAUCGGGAUCCUGAGGAGCCAGUGGGCUGCAGGCGCAGGCGCAGGCGAGGGGCUGGGUGGCGGUUGAGACAGCGGCGGUACUGGGAGGCGUAGGUGAGGGUCGCGAGGCUGCCCGAGCUUCUGAGCGAGCGCGGUGCUUUUGGGAACGCGGGACGGGCGAUCUGCGGCGCCAGGAGCUGGGCCGAGGCGCGGCGGCGCGGCUGCCGGCUGCCCUGUGAAUGGGAAGUUACGCGAAGUCCACCCAGCGUUUCUGAGGCAAUCUGAAGGCAAAUCCUGUUUAGACCCAGGCGAAGGUUCCCGGUGACCCGGGCUCUCACCAGCCAAUUGUCCCUUGCCGUCCUCCUGAGGGUGCCUGGAGCUUAAGCACUGUGUGCUCUUGGCCUCCACACUGGGGAUGCCGCUGACUCCCACUGUCCAGGGCUUCCAGUGGAUUCUCCGAGGCCCUGAUGUAGAAACUUCCCCAUUGGGUGCACCAAGAGCAGCCUCACAUGGUGUGGGCUGACAUCAAGAGCUGCCAGAUCCAACAGGGAGCCUUGGAAGGAGCCCGAAUCACUGAUGGAAUUGGACAGUGCAUGGAGAUGGUUCAGCAGGACAAGGUGCUGAAAACUCAUCCCCGUGUGACCUCAAUGUCAUUGGAGGACAGUGUGGAGUGCAGAGAGACAUGCUUUGAAAUGGGAUUGAUCCAGUGCUCCUUCCUUCACUACCACAUGAAUGCUGGGCAGCCCAGGGUCAACCCACCGCACCCUCAACUCAGGCAAGUCCAGCAGCCAAUCUUAGGAGACCUGGGCUACAGAACAGUCUCCCAAGUUCCAGGCUCACAAAACCUAGGUGGGGAUGAAAGCUGAGAAAGCGAGGAGGUGGUUCAGGGGAUCACUCUUUCCUACUCAUUCCUCUCAUCUCAAACUCACCUUCUACUGCAACACUGAGGAUCACCAACCAACCGUGACCAUAACCUUGAUCUUGCCAUGUUCUGUUAGUGGAAUGCAACCCAAAAUCAAUGGUGUUAGGUCAUCUGAACAAAAUAUAUAUCAAACCAUAUUGCAUAAGAACCACUCAUGGCCCUGUUCUUUUCAGUAUAUGGGAAAACAAAAUGGAAACAACAAAAUAGCAUCAGGUUUAUGAAACUUCCCAAGAUAGAUGGUCACACAUGUUUUCAGGAGAUCUCUAUAUAAAUGAUUUUGAUCACUUGAUACCUUGAAAAGAGCUCUUGUGACACUAGAAUGACAUCCAUAAGUGACAAGUAUAAAAUGUAGCGCUCAGUGACAUCAAAAACCAAAUCAACCCACAUAGAGGAAGAGCUCUGGACAUAGGGAUGUCAAACUGGUCUAGAGUGUAAUGAAAAGCAAAGAUGGUGGCCCAGUGAGAAAAAAGAAAUCAACAUAACAAUGGGAAACAGCAAGAAGAAUACUGAGACAGGAAAGACAACAUUUUUUACAAGUGAAUUAUUCAUUCACUUUCUAGUGGAUACAGACAAAACUGCAGAAGACCCAGAGGAAAUCAGGGCAGGCUAAAAGUUUGAUAUCUUACACCUGUGGAAAAGCCUUAAGCUCUGUUUUAACUGAGAGCAGGUGGGGUGACUUCAUGACUACCAUUAAGAAAAUACAACCUGUUGGGAAACUGUUUCUGCCUUGAUGAUGUUGUACAGACAAGAGAUAAACAGUGAGGAAUAUGCUUAGAUGUAUUGGGAAAGACACGGGUCUGUGGCAUCAUCACAAGGGUACACGAAUACUGAGAGUGAAUGCUGAAGGAAUGAUCCCCAUUGGUGGUGACCCUCAGGUGAGACUAGGGUGCCUGUGUUUCAGCAAAGCCUGGGCAAUUGGAAUGCAGGGCUCCUAAGAUUCCAUGACACCCCCACCUUCUAAUUCUGUUAUUGCAACUGCAGACGGUUACCUGGCACGCUGGCCACAGUCUACCUCACUCUUAUCAGAGUCUGAGCUACUGGCAGUGCUUUCAGCUGUGAGUUCAGGCACCUCAAACCUUGUUUUUGUGGUGAAGGAUCCUAAAGUGCUGUGGGGAGUGAUCACAUUUUUCA